GAGUCGGACAUGCUGUCCCCUGAGCCCACCUACUCCCAUCCUCCUUGGGAGAAGCAGCCUUACCUGGGCAGAGGCUCCAGGUCUUUUAGGGAGGACGUGGGCACUCCUGCCACGGAGGCAGCUGGCUGUGCCGCCAUCAGACUGGGCCCCAUGGUGUCACCAACUCCGCAGCGUCCAGGAGCCACCAGGAGGACAAAAUCGCAGCUUUGGCUGAACUGGAGCCUAGAGGCCAGGCUGUGCCUGCGGCUGCUCCUCAGGACCUACAGGGGACAGGACGGAGGGUGGGUGCUGAGCGUGCAUCCUCAGCUGGUCCUUGUCCUCAUCCUUAUCCCUGUCUCCAGCCCCGUCCAGAGUGCCCUGCUGCUGUCCUCCAGAUAGGCCUGUUUGCCGGCCUGGACGGAGCCCGUUCCUUUACUCUCCUUUUGUUUUCUCUUGACCAGAUCUAACUUCCUGAUUGCCGCCUUGUAAUAUCUAGAGAUUGGGGGUAAUUAUAACUCAAAGAGGCUUAACGAGCACUCGGAAAAGGUUGGAAUUAGCCCUCCGGCUUCUGCGCGCAGCUCUGUUGUGGAUGAAUCACUUCUGAAUGGACAGUUCUUUUCAGCUGUCCCGGGAGGCUUAGCAGAUGGGUGCUGCCUCCCUCCUGCUCCUGGCUGUACAGCUGCCUGGACACUGUGUCUAUUUAAGCCCCAUAAGCCCUUUUUAAAGCGAUUGCCAUGCUACCGGAGCAUAAUACGUAGGGUAUUUGAAUGCGAUUAAUUACCUCCAUUUCAUUGUAUAGCAAACGAUGGCUCCACUGGGUUACUUGAGGCCUGGGAUGAUGAAAAGUCAGAGCAAAUGAGCCCCUUUGCGCAGUGCAUUGAGAAAGCUCCCGUGCACCAAGAAGAGAGUGCUUUUGAGUCCCUGCAUGUUGGGAGGCGCCCGUGGACCUGCACCGUUUUGUUGCUGGUGUGCAUUGUGCAGAAGCGGGACACGGAGAAGAUGUACGCCAUGAAGUACAUGAACAAGCAGCAGUGCAUCGAGCGCGACGAGGUCCGCAACGUCUUCCGGGAGCUGGAGAUCCUGCAGGAGAUCGAGCACGUCUUCCUGGUGAACCUCUGGUACUCCUUCCAGGACGAGGAGGACAUGUUCAUGGUCGUGGACCUGCUACUGGGCGGGGACCUGCGCUACCACCUGCAGCAGAACGUGCAGUUCUCCGAGGACACGGUGAGGCUGUACAUCUGCGAGAUGGCACUGGCUCUGGACUACCUGCGCGGCCAGCACAUCAUCCACAGAGAUGUCAAGCCUGACAACAUUCUCCUGGAUGAGAGAGGACAUGCACACCUGACCGACUUCAACAUUGCCACCAUCAUCAAGGACGGGGAGCGGGCGACGGCAUUAGCAGGCACCAAGCCGUACAUGGCUCCGGAGAUCUUCCACUCUUUUGUCAACGGCGGGACCGGCUACUCCUUCGAGGUGGACUGGUGGUCGGUGGGGGUGAUGGCCUAUGAGCUGCUGCGAGGAUGGAGGCCCUAUGACAUCCACUCCAGCAACGCCGUGGAGUCCCUGGUGCAGCUGUUCAGCACCGUGAGCGUCCAGUAUGUCCCCACGUGGUCCAAGGAGAUGGUGGCCUUGCUGCGGAAGCUCCUCACUGUGAACCCCGAGCACCGGCUCUCCAGCCUCCAGGACGUGCAGGCAGCCCCGGCGCUGGCCGGCGUGCUGUGGGACCACCUGAGCGAGAAGAGGGUGGAGCCGGGCUUCGUGCCCAACAAAGGCCGUCUGCACUGCGACCCCACCUUUGAGCUGGAGGAGAUGAUCCUGGAGUCCAGGCCCCUGCACAAGAAGAAGAAGCGUCUGGCCAAGAACAAGUCCCGGGACAACAGCAGGGACAGCUCCCAGUCCGAGAAUGACUAUCUUCAAGACUGCCUCGAUGCCAUCCAGCAAGACUUCGUGAUUUUUAACAGAGAAAAGCUGAAGAGGAGCCAGGACCUCCCGAGGGAGCCUCUCCCCGCCCCUGAGUCCAGGGAUGCUGCGGAGCCUGUGGAGGACGAGGCGGAACGCUCCGCCCUGCCCAUGUGCGGCCCCAUUUGCCCCUCGGCCGGGAGCGGCUAGGCCGGGACGCCCGUGGUCCUCACCCCUUGAGCUGCUUUGGAGACUCGGCUGCCAGAGGGAGGGCCAUGGGCCGAGGCCUGGCAUUCACGUUCCCACCCAGCCUGGCUGGCGGUGCCCACAGUGCCCCGGACACAUUUCACACCUCAGGCUCGUGGUGGUGCAGGGGACAAGAGGCUGUGGGUGCAGGGGACACCUGUGGAGGGCAUUUCCCGUGGGCCCCCGAGACCCGCCUAGAUGGAGGAAGCGCUGCUGGGCGCCCUCUUACCGCUCACGGGGAGCUGGGGCCAUGGAUGGGACAGGAGUCUUUGUCCCUGCUCAGCCCGGAGGCUGUGCACGGCCCUCGUCACAAGGUGACCCUUGCAGCACAGGCCGCGGGUGCCCCAGGCUCGGCUCAGGUCUUGGAGGUCAAGGGCAUGGGUUGGGGUAGUGGGUGGGGAGGUGAAUGUUUUCUAGAGAUUCAAACUGCUCCAGCAAUUUCUGUAGUUUUCACCUCUGAGAAUUACAAUGUGAGAACCGCUCGAUGUUGCA